AAUAUCUCAGGACCCAGGACCAUGUGAUAUGGGCCCAACACCUGGAUGAUGUUACUCUUCUGCCUAGGUCAUGCGUAAAGAGGGAAUUAGGGCAUAUUGCUUGGCCCAGUCCCGUAAUGAUAUGACUCUCCUGCUUGUGCCAGAGCCACAGAAGUGUGCUUGGUGACAUAAUCUUUGAGGCUGUCACAUCACCAAGAUUAUAUUGUAUCACUGGACCAGCAUAAAGCUGACACUUCUGACUAUGCCCAGCCUUCAAAUAAUACUACACUGUAUAAUUGGCUCAACACCCAGGUGAUAUUGUUCCAUUUACCUGAGACCAGAUAAAAAGCCUAAUGAUGACGCUUGUCCCCAGAGCCAGGACACGUGCAGGACAGGAUCAUUACUCUCAUCCCUGCCCCAGAUUUUCACAGGUGCUGCUUACAGAGGGCAUCAUGACAUAUUGCUUGACAAAGAACCUAAGUGAUGUUAAUAUUCUGCAUAGGUUGCUAAAAAAUGGGAAUGUGAGAAAUACCUUGCUUCAGUCCAAAGUGGGCUUGCUGACAUAUUAUGUGAAACUGUACCCGGGUGAAGUGACUCUUCUGACUAGGCCCAGCAUACAAAUGAGAUUAUGCUGUAUCACUGGCUCAGUGUCGAGGCCCAGAUCACAGAAGUAAUUGUGCCAUAUGUGGAACAAGCAGCUAAGCAAUAGAUAACAUCCAUCGUGGCUCUGCCUUCAAAGGGAAAUUUUACAUAUGUCACUGGGACCAUCACCCAGAUGAUGUCCUGCCCACUAAAAGAAUUGUGACAUAACGCUGACUGCAAAAACUGGGUAAUGCAACUCUCCUCUUUAUUCUGGAGUCUGCCAAAACAAGGGAUUAUCACAUAUUGCGGAGUCCAGCACCCAGGUAAAAUUUUGUCAUAUACCCAGCUUCAGAUACCAUGCAAUAAUACAACUAUCAUACCUGGACCCAAAGAGGAGAGAUAUUUUGAUUCUCAUUGCCAUUCUUAUGGCCACAAGCAAAGUAAUGGUUCUCAUAGUGGUAUAAAGUUCACACAGUAUUAUGACACUCCCAGCGUAUCAUAGAAAAUGUGAGUAGUACAAUGAGUGUUAUAACAGGGAACAGCAAACCAAUGCUAUUGUGAUUAUUGGAUUCACACCCAGCUGACGCGACUAUCAUUCUCUCACAAGAACAGAACCUGCAAAUAAAGUACUAAAUCUCACCAAAA